GUUGUGACUGAAACCCGUCAAUAUGGCGGCGAUCGGCCGCGGCCGCUCUCUGAAGAACCUCCGAGUACGAGGGCGGAAUGACAGCGGCGAGGAGAACGUCCCGCUGGAUCUGACCCGAGAGUGAAAAUAUUAGAAAUUACAGAGCUACACAGAUAACGCUCUAGAGUAAAUGACAUCUCAUCCAAACUACUGAGAGUUUAGAACCUUCUGAUAACUUAAGAGAGAUUCUCCAAAAUGUGGCCAGAUUGCAGGGAGUAUCAAAUAUGAGAAAGCUAGGCCAUCUGAAUAACUUUACUAAGCUUCUUUGUGAUAUUGGCCACAGUGAAGAAAAACUGGGCUUUCACUAUGAGGAUAUCAUAAUUUGUUUGCGGUUAGCUUUAUUAAAUGAAGCAAAAGAAGUGCGAGCAGCAGGGCUACGAGCGCUUCGAUAUCUCAUCCAAGACUCCAGUAUUCUCCAGAAGGUGCUAAAAUUGAAAGUGGACUAUUUAAUAGCUAGGUGCAUUGACAUACAACAGAGCAACGAGGUAGAGAGGACACAAGCACUUCGAUUAGUCAGAAAGAUGAUUACUGUGAAUGCUUCCUUGUUUCCUAGUUCUGUGACCAACUCAUUAAUUGCAGUUGGAAAUGAUGGACUUCAAGAAAGAGACAGAAUGGUCCGAGCAUGCAUUGCCAUUAUCUGUGAACUAGCACUUCAGAAUCCAGAGGUGGUGGCCCUUCGAGGUGGACUAAACACCAUCUUGAAAAAUGUGAUCGAUUGCCAAUUAAGUCGAAUAAAUGAGGCCCUAAUUACUACAAUUUUGCACCUUCUUAAUCAUCCAAAGACUCGACAGUAUGUGCGAGCUGAUGUAGAAUUAGAGAGAAUUUUAGCACCCUAUACUGAUUUUCACUACAGACAUAGUCCAGAUACAGCUGAAGGACAGCUCAAAGAAGACAGAGAAGCACGAUUUCUAGCCAGUAAAAUGGGAAUCAUAGCAACAUUCCGAUCAUGGGCAGGUAUUAUUAAUUUAUGUAAACCUGGAAAUUCUGGGAUCCAGUCUCUAAUAGGAGUACUUUGCAUACCAAAUAUGGAAAUAAGGCGAGGUCUACUUGAAGUGCUUUAUGAUAUAUUUCGUCUUCCUCUACCUGUUGUGACUGAGGAGUUCAUAGAAGCACUACUCAGUGUAGAUCCAGGGAGGUUCCAAGACAGUUGGAGGCUUUCAGAUGGCUUUGUGGCAGCUGAGGCAAAAACUAUUCUUCCUCAUCGUGCCAGAUCCAGGCCAGACCUCAUGGAUAAUUAUUUGGCACUGAUACUCUCUGCAUUUAUUCGUAAUGGACUUUUAGAGGGUCUAGUUGAAGUGAUAACAAACAGUGAUGAUCAUAUCUCAGUUAGAGCUACCAUCCUUUUAGGAGAGCUUUUACAUAUGGCAAACACAAUUCUUCCUCAUUCACAUAGCCAUCAUUUACACUGCUUGCCAACCCUAAUGAAUAUGGCUGCAUCCUUUGAUAUCCCCAAGGAAAAGAGACUGCGAGCCAGUGCAGCCUUGAACUGUUUAAAACGCUUCCAUGAAAUGAAGAAACGAGGACCUAAGCCUUAUAGUCUUCAUUUAGACCACAUUAUUCAGAAAGCAAUUGCAACACACCAGAAACGGGAUCAGUAUCUCCGAGUUCAGAAAGAUAUAUUUAUCCUUAAGGAUACAGAGGAAGCUCUUUUAAUUAACCUUAGAGAUAGCCAAGUCCUUCAACAUAAAGAGAAUCUUGAAUGGAAUUGGAAUCUUAUAGGGACCAUUCUUAAGUGGCCAAAUGUAAAUCUAAGAAACUAUAAAGAUGAACAGUUACACAGGUUUGUACGAAGACUACUUUAUUUUUACAAGCCCAGCAGUAAAUUAUAUGCCAACCUGGAUCUGGAUUUUGCCAAGGCCAAACAGCUCACGGUUGUAGGUUGCCAGUUUACAGAAUUUCUUCUUGAAUCUGAAGAGGAUGGGCAAGGCUACUUAGAAGAUCUAGUAAAGGAUAUUGUUCAGUGGCUCAAUGCUUCAUCUGGAAUGAAACCCGAAAGAAGUCUUCAAAAUAAUGGUUUAUUGACCACCCUUAGUCAACACUACUUUUUAUUUAUUGGAACACUUUCUUGCCACCCUCAUGGAGUUAAAAUGCUGGAAAAAUGCAGUGUAUUUCAGUGUCUCCUUAAUCUUUGCUCCUUGAAAAACCAAGAUCACUUGCUAAAACUUACUGUUUCUAGCUUGGACUAUAGCAGAGAUGGAUUGGCUAGAGUCAUCCUUUCCAAAAUUUUAACUGCAGCUACUGAUGCCUGCAGACUCUAUGCAACAAAACAUUUAAGGGUAUUAUUGAGAGCUAAUGUUGAAUUCUUUAAUAAUUGGGGAAUUGAGUUGUUAGUGACCCAGCUACAUGAUAAAAACAAAACGAUUUCCUCUGAAGCUCUUGAUAUCCUCGAUGAAGCAUGUGAAGACAAGGCCAAUCUUCAUGCUCUCAUUCAGAUGAAACCAGCGUUAUCCCACCUUGGAGACAAGGGUUUGCUUCUCCUGCUGAGAUUUCUCUCCAUUCCAAAAGGAUUUUCCUAUCUGAAUGAAAGAGGUUAUGUAGCAAAACAAUUGGAAAAGUGGCACAGGGAAUACAACUCCAAAUAUGUUGACUUGAUUGAGGAACAACUCAAUGAAGCACUUACUACUUACCGGAAGCCUGUUGAUGGUGAUAACUAUGUUCGUCGGAGUAACCAAAGAUUACAGCGUCCUCACGUCUACCUGCCUAUACACCUUUAUGGACAACUAGUACACCAUAAAACAGGCUGCCAUUUGUUGGAAGUACAGAAUAUUAUUACAGAACUCUGUCGUAAUGUUCGUACACCAGAUUUGGAUAAGUGGGAAGAAAUUAAAAAACUGAAAGCAUCUCUUUGGGCCUUGGGAAAUAUCGGCUCAUCAAAUUGGGGUCUCAAUUUGCUACAGGAAGAAAACGUGAUUCCAGAUAUACUAAAACUUGCAAAACAGUGUGAAGUUCUUUCCAUCAGAGGGACCUGUGUAUAUGUACUUGGGCUCAUAGCUAAAACCAAACAAGGCUGUGAUAUUCUAAAAUGUCACAACUGGGAUGCUGUGAGGCAUAGUCGCAAACAUCUGUGGCCAGUGGUUCCAGAUGAUGUGGAACAACUCUGUAAUGAACUUUCAUCUAUCCCAAGCACUCUAAGUUUGAACUCGGAGUCAACCAGCUCUAGACAUAAUAGUGAAAGUGAAUCUGUGCCAUCGAGUAUGUUCAUAUUGGAGGAUGACCGGUUUGGCAGCAGCUCUACUAGCACAUUUUUCCUUGAUAUCAAUGAAGAUACAGAGCCAACAUUUUAUGACCGAUCUGGACCCAUAAAGGAUAAAAAUUCAUUCCCUUUCUUUGCUUCUAGUAAACUUGUGAAGAAUCGUAUCUUAAAUUCGCUUACUUUGCCUAACAAAAAACAUCGUAGUAGCAGUGAUCCAAAAGGAGGGAAAUUAUCAUCUGAAAGUAAGACAAGCAACAGGCGAAUCAGAACACUUACGGAGCCCAGUGUUGAUUUUAAUCAUAGUGAUGAUUUUACACCCAUAUCCACUGUACAGAAAACAUUACAAUUAGAGACUUCAUUUAUGGGGAAUAAGCACAUUGAAGACACUGGUAGUACACCAAGCAUUGGAGAAAAUGACUUAAAAUUCACCAAGAAUUUUGGUACAGAGAAUCACAGAGAAAAUACAAGCCGAGAGAGGUUAGUAGUAGAAAGUUCAACGAGCUCACAUAUGAAGAUACGUAGCCAAAGUUUCAAUACAGACACUACAACAAGUGGCAUAAGUUCAAUGAGCUCAAGUCCUUCACGAGAGACAGUAGGUGUAGAUGCUACAACUAUGGACACAGACUGUGGAAGCAUGAGUACUGUGGUAAGUACUAAAACUAUUAAGACAAGCCACUAUUUGACGCCACAGUCUAACCAUCUGUCUCUCUCCAAAUCAAAUUCGGUGUCCCUGGUGCCUCCAGGUUCUUCUCAUACGCUUCCUAGAAGAGCACAGUCCCUUAAAGCACCCUCUAUUGCUACAAUUAAAAGUCUAGCAGAUUGUAACUUUAGUUACACAAGUUCUAGAGAUGCUUUUGGCUAUGCUACACUGAAAAGACUACAGCAACAAAGAAUGCAUCCAUCCUUAUCUCACUCUGAAGCUUUGGCAUCUCCAGCAAAAGAUGUGCUAUUUACUGAUACCAUCACCAUGAAGGCCAACAGUUUUGAGUCCAGAUUAACACCAAGCAGGAUCGAUUUUAAAAAGAAGCAUGUCGGGGGAAUCAGGAGCUUAAGACCUACAAUAACAAACAACCUUUUCAGGUUCAUGAAAGCCUUAAGUUAUGCAUCAUUAGAUAAAGAAGAUUUAUUGAGUCCUAUUAAUCAAAAUACCCUGCAACGAUCUUCCUCAGUGCGGUCCAUGGUGUCCAGUGCCACAUAUGGGGGUUCAGAUGAUUACAUUGGUCUUGCUCUCCCGGUGGAUAUAAAUGAUAUAUUCCAGGUAAAGGAUAUUCCCUAUUUUCAGACAAAAAACAUACCACCACAUGAUGAUCGAGGUGCAAGAGCAUUUGCCCAUGAUGCAGGAGGUCUUCCAUCUGGAACUGGAGGUCUUGUAAAAAAUUCUUUUCACUUGCUACGACAGCAGAUGAGUCUUACGGAAAUAAUGAAUUCAAUCCAUUCAGAUGCCUCUCUGUUUUUAGAAAGUACAGAAGACACUGGACUACAGGAACAUACAGAUGAUAACUGCCUUUAUUGUGUCUGUAUUGAAAUUCUGGGUUUCCAGCCCAGCAACCAACUGAGUGCAAUAUGUAGUCAUUCAGACUUUCAAGAUAUUCCAUAUUCUGAUUGGUGUGAGCAGACUAUCCAUAAUCCUUUAGAAGUGGUUCCCUCUAAGUUUUCGGGGAUUUCUGGAUGCAGUGAUGGGGUGUCUCAAGAAGGCUCAGCUAGCAGCACCAAAAGCACAGAAUUGUUACUAGGUGUUAAAACAAUUCCAGAUGAUACACCAAUGUGCCGUAUACUCCUUCGCAAAGAAGUUCUAAGAUUAGUCAUUAAUUUGAGUAGUUCAGUUUCAACUAAAUGUCAUGAGACUGGGCUUUUAACAAUUAAGGAGAAGUAUCCUCAAACAUUUGAUGACAUAUGCCUUUACUCUGAGGUUUCCCAUUUGCUGUCACACUGCACAUUCAGACUUCCGUGUCGGAGGUUCAUACAAGAAUUAUUUCAAGAUGUACAGUUUCUACAAAUGCAUGAAGAAGCAGAGGCUGUGUUGGCAACACCACCAAAGCAACCUAUAGUUGAUACAUCUGCUGAAUCCUGACCUCAUAUUUAUGAUGGAUAUAGAUACAUACUAUAUAUAUUCAUAUUUGUGGAUUUCCUAAAAGCCUCAGAAAAUACGACUGACUAGGCAGCAAAGACAGGAGUAUCUUCUGUACACUGUUCCGCAGUUACUGGUACAUGAACAGUUGGAACUGCUGACUUUCCUAACCAAAACAACUUCCUUCUCUCCUUUGUUGAGCCUUUUGAGGGGUUCAUGAUUCAUUACCACAGUUUUAAGAGUUUCAGUUACCAUUGUAUGCAAGAGCCAAGCACUGAAUACCUACAUAGGUUUUCUAUUUUCUUUCAUUUUAAAAGCAUAAUGACAGUGGAACAAUAAUGGGAUAUGCAGAAGCACCCUUCACAAGUUAUUUCUGAAUGAUUUUUAGGGUAAAUAAUACAGAUGCCUUGUUUGUUAACUAACUUGUGGAAAGCAGGAAUCAGUGUCUCUAAGGCUGCAUCCUAUUACCACAAUGGGGUGUGCUAUAACUGCUGGUAUUAGAGAGGGAACUUUGGCCCUUUCACGUUUUUCUUAAUGUUUGUAACACUACUUCAGAGGUUUAUAACCUCAAAGCAGAAGAAGAGCCUCAACAACCCGGGACUUAUAAGUUAUUUUUAUGUUACUAGACUUGCAUAAAGAUUCUUGUUUUCCAACUCUUCAUUUUGUUGCAAUGUGUUAUUACAGGAUAUAUGAACCAAUUAAGGUUUUUCACUACAGUUCUUGAAUAAAAUUUAAAAAUCAUUUUUUAUUUUAAUUAAAAAUAUUUCCCAUUUAUAGAAUGCAUAUAUUUGCAAUGGACUUCCACUUUCAUCAACUUUCCAUCUCAUCGCUUUAAACAGGAACUUGAACAAGCACUGUUAGUUUAGACCUAAAGGAUAGGAAAGCAUUAAAUAAUACUUUGGAUCUCCUGAGGAAAAGAUAAGUUUGCUUGCAAUUUACACAUUCCAUGGGGAAAGAAGAGCCAUAUUUCCUUAAAAAAAACAUUAAUAAAGCUUGUUAUUGAGAAAAAUUGUAGUGAAAAGCCUUAAGUACCAAAUUUUAAAGCAGCAGUAACUUAAUUUUUAUAUCAGUGUUUUUGUUUUGCACAAACUAAAUGCAGUGGUAGGUGGGUUUAUGAGUAUAUUAAUUGCCUUUAUCCAUUUGUGAAGUUAAGUUGAUGAGGGCAAGGUUUUUGUUUGUUUAAUUUGUAUAUGUCUAAAGGUAUUUGGAACUUUUUACAGGAAUUAAACAUAUAUGCAAAUUUGUAUAUAAAAAUAGCAUGGCCAUCAUUUGAAUGCUUGUAAAUGAAAGGAUUAUCUUUUUUGAGAUCUAUAUAUAAAUAGAAAUAGAAAAUCCAGCUGGACUGAUUAGGAUUCUUUUUUAAUUCAUUUGUGUAUAACAUUUUUAUUACAAUUACACAUCAGUUUUGACACAGUCAUAGCAACAUUAAUAUUUUCCCAUGAUGCAGAUCCUUUUUGUAAUGGGCUUGUUCUUUGAGAUCUCUGUAAAGAACCCUGUGAACUAGAAAACAUAACUCACAGAGAUACUUUUUUAAAAAAUUUAUUUACUGGAACUGAAAGUUCCAGUUGGGAUGAAGCAUUUCAUCUCACUUCAUAACACCUCUUUGACUGCACUUCAGUGAAUUGUUCUUAUGUGCACUGUGUAGCAACUUACAUUAUAACAAAGCAGAUAAGGGCUGUAAGCUGCUGCUUAUGUUGAAAAGUGGUUCUUCAGAUUUUCUCUCAUAAAAUCCAGUUGAAGAUAAAUAAUUUUUUUAUACUUUAUCACUGAACCCAAGUGUUUAUUUAAAUGUCAACAGUACUUCUAAGAACGUUGCCUGUCAUCGUGGUCUUUGGUCUUGGAUAACUAAACUGCCUUUCCAGAGAACCAAAUGUCAGAGUUACUAGACCAAAUAGUGGUUAAAACCUCCAAAGGAAGUAAUGUAAUCUUAUUCAUAAUGGGAUUAACAUAUUUUAGACAUUCAUUUUAAACACUACCUCAGUUAAUAUAGAGUAUAAAAAUCUGUGGUUUAAUCCCUCAAAAGUUAACAGUAAUUUUUUUUUUGUCUUACACACACACACACCCCCUCCCCCACCAUCACUAUCCCUGUACCCUCACCUUGGUCAUCUAUCCUGAAAUAAGGCUUAGUUAGUAUUGGCCUGAAUGUUUUGUGUUUUUUUUUUUGUUUUUUUUUUUUACUGUUACUUUGAAAAAUAUGUAUGUAUACCUUAUCAUAUCUGCCUAUAUCACUUACUUUGGGGAGAUACUCAGAGCUUUGUGGUUAUCAGUAUACUAAAAAAAAAAAAAAGUCUACGCUUAAAUUUAUAGUGCUAUUUGGUUUCUCCAUGAUUUCACUGACAGGUCUAAUACAUUUUCUUUGAGUACUUGUUUGUAAAAAGUAGACUUUAUGGUGAAAAAUACAUGCAGUGCCAAGUGAUUAACUUAAGUGUUUAAAAAUAUUAAAUUAUAGCAGAAGAGGUUAGGAAUGAUAUCAGCAGUAAUAGAAAUAAUUGAGAAAAUCAUCUAUAAAUAAUAGAUAUUACAGACUAUAGAAUACCAAAAUAAUGUCAAUACUGUAGUUUUUAAAGAUUUUAGGAUUAAUCUUAGUCCAUAUAAAUUUGUACUAUUGGUAAUUAUUGAAUAAUUGGGAGGAAUCUGGGCAGUUGUGCUGGUUGUAAACUAUGAAUUUCUAAUCGUAAAGUGAAUUGUUAUUUCUAAUUGAACUUUUUUUCAAGAACAGAUUUCAGCCUCACAUACUAAGUAAAUACUGAUAAAUAAGGAAAUUAGAAAUUUAGUAUUCAUAAUUAAAUAUGCUCUAAAAUUUCCUAUACUUUUAUUUCCUGUUUAUUCUUAGGUAGAUUGGAAGGGGGAAACAGUCUGUUCUCCCUAAUUAAAUUUUUUCUAAUAACGAUUAGUAGAAUAUGGACAUUCUAUAUGACAGUGACAUUAAAAGAGGCUCUUUGGAAGUAUAUACAUUAUUAACAUAAUGUGUACAAGUCCUUUUGAAAUGACAACUUUAAUGGGUUUCAGCUCUUUUAUCUAGAGCUUGAGAUAAUUCAAGCUGAGUUUUUCAGGGCAUAUCACAACGGCCAAGUGUUCAGCAGUGGGAUAUCAAUGCUUAUUUACAUUUUCCUACUGCUAUUUAUAUAAAAUGUUAUUCCAUUCAGAGGAUGCCUUUUAUCCCCACAUUAAAGCACAGAUCAUUAAGCAAUAAAAACCAAAUUGUCUGUCAUUCAAAUUAUAACUGCAGUUAUUUUUGCAUGGUAAGAGUGAGGUGCUAAUUUUGUGUGAGAUGAACUUUGUAAACUACUUUGGGAAAUGUUCUUUGGAAGUAAGGUUUUUUCUCCUUUAGUCUUAUGCUUCCACUUUUGUCUCAGAUUCACAAUCCAUUAAAACAUGGGGAAAAAAGAAAAGGUAAAAUUGAGAGACUUUUGUUAGAGGAGCUAUUUGGAAUGAACCAACAUUUCAGAUUUUCCAAAAUGUAAGUUAGGAAGUCUCCAUUGUCUCUGCAUUAACAAAAUACACUGUUACUAUCUUAAUCUCAAGAGUGUCAUUACAGUGAGAAUCUCAUUUAAAAGCAUACCAGUGAAAUUAAUAGCAGUGCUUAUCAAAGAACACUGAAAUCUGUGAGAAUCUUUCUAGGAGCAUUCUUUUCUUCUUUUAGUUCCAAGUUCCAGGGUAUUUUUCAUUCCUAGUAGGUUUAUAUGACUCACAGAAUGUGGACUUUUUUCCUGUUUGGAGUAUUUUUGUAAUGUAAGUAUCGGAUAGCUGCACCACAGCAUGCAUAAAUUGCACAUUUUGUUUUACUUUCUUUAUAGAAUAUUUAAUUUCAAAAAUAUAAUUUAUGCCAAAAAAAGCAUACCUUUCAAUUUUGCUACUUGGUUGAUUUAGCACAAAAUGCAAAGUCUUGGGGCAGAGAGGGGGAGUGAAAAAAAUUUUAUAGGUAAUUGUUACAAAAAUACCUGUCAGAAACCCUAAAGCUGCAUUGUAAAACAAAUGGUGUAAACUAGUUUUGAAAAGUGGUAAGGAAUUGUGAAAAAAAUCUCAGACUUAAUGCUCUCUAACCACAUGAGUUUCUUCUUUUUUAUUUAGUAAUACGCUGCUACAUAUUUGGAGGUUCUGGUGUUUGUAGGUCACUGAACAGACAUUGAAAUCUGAUUUAUAUUGUAUAACUGUAACAUAGAAAGAAAAAGUAUUUAUAUUUUUUCUGUAAGAAUAUUUCAUUGAGUUGUGUAUAAUUUAAAUAAGAUUUGUCCCCAAAUGGUUUUGCUCACCUUGAUUUUUUUUGUUGUGAUUUUCUUGUUUUUGUAUAAUGUGUAUAGUUUAUGUCAAGGGCAUUAAAAGCCUCCUGAAGCAUAAUCUUAUCAAAGGGAUACAUUGUUAAUAAAAUGUACUUAAAAUUCUUAAA